CUCUGCUCUGGACUUGGGAGGCUCCGUUGCCUGCUCCCGGAGGGAGACGCGCUGCCGAGGAGAACCCAGCGGGAGAACAUUUCAGGAUAGGAAUAGGCCAAGUGCUGAGAAGAUGAGUCUUAGGAUUGAUGUGGAUACAAACUUUCCUGAGUGUGUUGUAGAUGCAGGAAAAGUCACCCUUGGGACUCAGCAGAGGCAGGAGAUGGACCCUCGCCUGCGGGAGAAACAGAAUGAAAUCAUCCUGCGAGCAGUAUGUGCUCUGCUGAAUUCUGGUGGGGGCAUAAUCAAGGCUGAGAUUGAGAACAAAGGCUACAAUUAUGAACGUCAUGGAGUAGGAUUGGAUGUGCCUCCAAUUUUCAGAAGCCAUUUAGAUAAGAUGCAGAAGGAAAACCACUUUUUGAUUUUUGUGAAAUCAUGGAACACAGAGGCUGGUGUGCCACUUGCUACCUUAUGCUCCAAUUUGUACCACAGAGAGAGAACAUCCACCGAUGUCAUGGAUUCUCAGGAAGCUCUGGCAUUCCUCAAAUGCAGGACUCAGACUCCAACGAAUAUUAAUGUUUCCAAUUCAUUAGGUCCACAGGCAGCUCAGGGUAGUGUACAAUAUGAAGGUAACAUAAAUGUGUCAGCUGCUGCUUUAUUUGAUAGAAAGCGGCUUCAGUAUCUGGAAAAACUCAACCUUCCUGAGUCCACACAUGUUGAAUUUGUAAUGUUCUCGACAGACGUGUCACACUGUGUUAAAGACAGACUUCCGAAGUGUGUUUCUGCAUUUGCAAAUACUGAAGGAGGAUAUGUAUUUUUUGGUGUGCAUGAUGAGACUUGUCAAGUGAUUGGAUGUGAAAAAGAGAAAAUAGACCUUACGAGCUUGAGGGCUUCUAUUGAUGGCUGUAUUAAGAAGCUACCUGUCCAUCAUUUCUGCACACAGAGGCCUGAGAUAAAAUAUGUCCUUAACUUCCUUGAAGUGCAUGAUAAGGGGGCCCUCCGUGGAUAUGUCUGUGCAAUCAAGGUGGAGAAAUUCUGCUGUGCGGUGUUUGCCAAAGUGCCUAGUUCCUGGCAGGUGAAGGACAACCGUGUGAGACAAUUGCCCACAAGAGAAUGGACUGCUUGGAUGAUGGAAGCUGACCCAGACCUUUCCAGGUGUCCUGAGAUGGUUCUCCAGUUGAGUUUGUCAUCUGCCACGCCCCGCAGCAAGCCUGUGUGCAUUCAUAAGAAUUCGGAAUGUCUGAAAGAGCAGCAGAAACGCUACUUUCCAGUAUUUUCAGACAGAGUGGUAUAUACUCCAGAAAGCCUCUACAAGGAACUCUUCUCACAACAUAAAGGACUCAGAGACUUAAUAAAUACAGAAAUGCGCCCUUUCUCUCAAGGAAUAUUGAUUUUUUCUCAAAGCUGGGCUGUGGAUUUAGGUCUGCAAGAGAAGCAGGGAGUCAUCUGUGAUGCUCUUCUAAUUUCCCAGAACAACACCCCUAUUCUCUACACCAUCUUCAGCAAGUGGGAUGCGGGGUGCAAGGGCUAUUCUAUGAUAGUUGCCUAUUCUUUGAAGCAGAAGCUGGUGAACAAAGGCGGCUACACUGGGAGGUUAUGCAUCACCCCCUUGGUCUGUGUGCUGAAUUCUGAUAGAAAAGCACAGAGCGUUUACAGUUCGUAUUUACAAAUUUACCCUGAAUCCUAUAACUUCAUGACCCCCCAGCACAUGGAAGCCCUGUUACAGUCCCUCGUGAUAGUCUUGCUUGGGUUCAAAUCCUUCUUAAGUGAAGAGCUGGGCUCUGAGGUUUUGAACCUACUGACAAAUAAACAGUAUGAGUUGCUUUCAAAGAACCUUCGCAAGACCAGAGAGUUGUUUGUUCAUGGCUUACCUGGAUCAGGGAAGACUAUCUUGGCUCUUAGGAUCAUGGAGAAGAUCAGGAAUGUGUUUCACUGUGAACCGGCUAACAUUCUCUACAUCUGUGAAAACCAGCCCCUGAAGAAGUUGGUGAGUUUCAGCAAGAAAAACAUCUGCCAGCCAGUGACCCGGAAAACCUUCAUGAAAAACAACUUUGAACACAUCCAGCACAUUAUCAUUGAUGACGCUCAGAAUUUCCGUACUGAAGAUGGGGACUGGUAUGGGAAAGCAAAGUUCAUCACUCAGACAGCAAGGGAUGGCCCAGGAGUUCUCUGGAUCUUUCUGGACUACUUUCAGACCUAUCACUUGAGUUGCAGUGGCCUCCCCCCUCCCUCAGACCAGUAUCCAAGAGAAGAGAUCAACAGAGUGGUCCGCAAUGCAGGUCCAAUAGCUAAUUACCUACAACAAGUAAUGCAGGAAGCCCGACAAAAUCCUCCACCUAACCUCCCCCCUGGGUCCCUGGUGAUGCUCUAUGAACCUAAAUGGGCUCAAGGUGUCCCAGGCAACUUAGAGAUUAUUGAAGACUUGAACUUGGAGGAGAUACUGAUCUAUGUAGCGAAUAAAUGCCGUUUUCUCUUGCGGAAUGGUUAUUCUCCGAAGGAUAUUGCUGUGCUUUUCACCAAAGCAAGUGAAGUGGAAAAAUAUAAAGACAGGCUUCUAACAGCAAUGAGGAAGAGAAAACUGUCUCAGCUCCAUGAGGAGUCUGAUCUGUUACUACAGAUCGGUGAUGCGUCGGAUGUUCUAACCGAUCACAUUGUGUUGGACAGUGUCUGUCGAUUUUCAGGCCUGGAAAGAAAUAUCGUGUUUGGAAUCAAUCCAGGAGUAGCCCCACCGGCUGGGGCCUACAAUCUUCUGCUCUGUUUGGCUUCUAGGGCAAAAAGACAUCUGUAUAUUCUGAAGGCUUCUGUGUGACAGGAAACCCAAGCCUAAGAAACAAUUAAGUGGUUCUCAUCUCUAAUUAACUGUGAAACCAUUUAAUCCAAACAUGUAAGCACACACUCACUUAUUAAGUCACAUACUUUUCUAGGUGCUGGGGAUUGAGAACGAAUCGAUGUAAGAUUCCUCCUUUAGGGCAGAGACAGACCACUGACAAAUACACAGAUAGACAAGGAAUUUCCCAUGGUAAAAAGGGAUAUCAGUAAUUAGAGGACCGUGAGACUCAGAGAUGUGUGUGUGUGUGUGUGUGUGUGUGUGUGUGUGUGCGCGCGCGCACGUGCACAUGUGUGUAGGUAGAUGGAGGGGGUGAUUAUUUUGGGUGGUCAGGGAAGUGCUCAGUGAGGGAAGAACUUGUCAUGAGAAUCUCUGAGCGUGCCAGGCAGACUCGGAUAUUUUUAUAAAUUUUUAACAUGGCCACUUGCAGAAGAGCUUGAAUGGGACGUGCAGCGAGAAUGUGAAGGAUGGAGCAGGUAGCUCAUCUGGCCUUGUAGGUGCCGGGAACGGGCAAGACAUGUUUUGAAAUGUAAGAUCACAGACUGUUUUUUGCAAGACCACAUUAUAUUACUUUAUUAUUUUCUGCUUUUUCUUUUAACGACAUUAGUGUUUUUGAUCACUAUAUUUUAAAAUGCUUUUUGUGAGCCUUUUGGUUAUGUGGAAUCUGUUCCUUAGCUCUGAUUUUUUAUUCUUAUGGAGCGUCUUAGGUUACUACAUGAAGGUAAGACUGCCACAGUCCCCCAGGGAGGCACACUGUGUUUUACUGAUUGAUUUGAAGAUGAUAGAGAGCCUAGGGGGAUGAGUCUAUUGGACUCAAAGGUUACAUUUUGUUUUUCCAUUUAAUUUAAUAAUCAACAAAACGACAAAGUCAGUUUAAUAUCUUUCUUCUGCUGAGUCUUCAGGAUGUUAGCUAGUCUUUCAAAAGCCAUUGCUACAAAAGUGCAAAUUUCUCAUUUCCUGUGGGUCUCUAGAAACUCUCUCAAUAUUUAAAGCCAAACAAAUCCAUCUUUUCUGAGAGACAGAAACUAAAAAAUUCAGAGUUAAUUCACUAUUAAAAACAGCAAGGCCCUGCUAUUUCCCAAGAAUAAAGAAAUUUAAAAUUCUCAUUGUAAGAAGUAUGAACUUGAAGCUAGAAUUGGUUUAUUUCUGGCAGCUACUUACAAUAUUAAGAACUUUACUUUUUAAAUUUGAGACAAUUUCACAGGAAAGCAAGAAAUUAGUCUAUUGUGAAAUGUUUUUACAACUAACUUGGAAUAUACUGCAAAUCACUAGUAAGUAGAGACACAUUUAAGAUAAAAUGAUUAAUAAAACAAUUGGUAAUUCUGAAUAAGGAUCUGAAUAAAUCCAGAUCACAGACUGUUCCUUUACCAAUAUGUAAAAGAAUGUGCAAAAUUAGUAAAAAUAUACCCAAAAAUUUACCAGCAACAGAGAAGCAAAGAAUGGAGUUCAACCUUACACUAUAAACAUCUAAUAGAUAUGUAUGAAAAUUUAAAAACUAGAAAAGGUUGGGCAUGGUGGCUCAUGCUUGUGAUCCCAGGACUUUAGGAGGCCAAGGUGGGAGGAUUGUUUGAGCCCAGGAGUUCAAGACCAGCUUGAGCAAUAUAGUGAGACCCUGUCUCUACAAAAACAAACAAACAAACAAACAAAUAAAUAAAUAAAUAAAAUUAGCUGGGAAUGGUGAUGCACACCUGGAGUCCUAGCUACUCAGAAGGCUGAGGCAGGACGAUCACUUGACCUCAGAAGUCUGAGGUUACAGUGAGCUAUGAUCAUACCAGUGCACUCCAGUCUGGGUGACAGAACAAGACCCUGUCUCCAAAAAUUAAAUAAAUAAAACAAAAAAAAAGAAUUUAAAAGUUUUAUAUAAAGGCAUAGCUACUAUCUCAUCUGCCCAGUGUAGUCAUGAAUAGAUGUCACAUAAAGAAAAGAAAACCAGAAUUCUUGUUAAUAUGGCCAGUUUGAAGGGUGGUGGCGGAGGUAUUGAGCAGGCAGCUCAGGGAAAUGCCAGGGAGACCCUUGAGCACAGAAACUCCUGAUUGUCCCCAGGGACUCUCCGUGGACACAGGAGGGAUUUUCCAGGAUUUCACAUGAAUUCAAUGAAGGGGGCUGUGUCUUAUUCCUGGAUGCUUUGCCUCCUUCAUGGAAUUCAGUGGAUUUAAUGGAAGUUCCUAGGCAACAAUAAAGAGUAGAAACCAGGUUAACAGCGAGGGCCUCAUCUCACACCAGAUCAUAUCAGGCUACACAAAAGUAGAUGGAAGACACCACCCAGGCCUCCAGCUAUACACUGGAGAAGAAGCCAAACUAGUCUACUUCAUCUAAGAAAGUUGUCAAAGAGAGCCCUUCUAUACUAUCUUAAGGUAAAAAGAAAGACUCUACCCAGCUGCCCUGAUUAAGCAUUAGAAAGAUAAGUGUUCUGAUCAUUAGGCGAAAGACAAUGGGGAAAAAUGUAGAAAAGAAAUAUGACAUGAGCCAGAUGAAGAACCCAUCCUGAAAGGAUAUAUAACUCAGGGGACAAAAGACAACUCACCAUAAGUUGGGCGCAGUGGAUCACGCCUGUAAUCUCAGCAUUUUGGUAGGCCAAGGCAGGUGGAUCACCUGAGGUCAGGAGUUCAAGUCCAGCCUGGCCAACGUGGUGAAAUCCUGUCUCUACUAAAAAUACAAAAAUUAGCUGGGUGUGGUGGUGCAUGCCUGUAAUACCAGCUACUCAGAAGGCUGAGGCAAGAGAAUUGCUUGAAUCAAGGAGGCAGAGGUUACAGUGAGCCAAGAUCAGGCCAUUGUACUUCAGCCUGGGCGACAAAGUGAGACCCUGUCUCAAAAAACAAACAAAGCCUCCCCAUAGAUGUCUCCUGCCAUAGAAGAAUUUAAGAAGUUCAUAAAUUCAAUAAAACAAGAGUUGAAGGCCUGUCCCACUGUACCCAAUUUCUCCCUCUCUGAACUGCAGCCUAGAAACUCUCUACAGGCAGUAAGCUGGGGCAGUCACAGAGGUGACCUCAUCUGUUUCCCACAUCCUGCAUUAGGACAGUGAUCAGGGAUCAGUAUCCUUCAUUGACUGAUUUCCAAUAUCUCGAGACCUGUUGUUUCAUAUAUUUUGCCUUAUUUUGCAAUUGUUUCAUAUAUUUUGUCUUAUUUUGCAAUUGUUUCAGGAGGGAGGAUAAAUAUGGUCCCUGUUCCUCUAUCUUGACCAGAAGCAUCUAAGAAGGCAGUGAAGCAACAUGUGUACAGUUCUUAGGGAAACAAAUUUUGACCUAAAAAUAUUAAACCUAGUCAAAAUAUUAUUCUAGUACAAAGGCAGCACAUGGGUAUUUUUGAACAUAAAAGAGUUCUAGAAAUACAGGACCCAUGAAUCAUUCUUGAAGAAAAGUUACUCAGUAAGGAAAUCUAGCUAAGCAAGCAACAUGUACAAAUAAAAGAUUAUUAUAAUUGGACCAAAGUUAAGUUUAAAUCCAUUCACAUGUAUAUAAUUAAGAUAUAUAGGAAUUAUAAUUACAGAAAAGAAUGUUACAAACCUUCACAAAGUAAAAAUAUUUUUAUAUCAGAUAGAUUCUUCUGUUUCAAUCCAUAAAACCAGGGUUUGGAUCAUUUUAAAAAAACAAACAAAAAUAAUUUAUUGGAAUCAUUAGGGAGGACCUGAUAGAAUAAAAUGACAAGCUGACCAAAUAGGCCUUAGAAGGGAGAGGUGCCUGGGCAGUUACAAGGACCUAGGUAGCAGGGGUGACUUGGCCACAGUCAUUUUCUUUACUUGAUUUAAGGAGGUUAAAUUACAGUGAGAGAGUUGCACUUAUUUAGUUUGCAUACCGUACUCAACUCUUAGCUAGCAUAGGGCAGGUUCCUUAGUUGAAAAAUUUCCACAAAACAUGAUGUAAAGUGGAAAGAUCAGUUCCCCCAAAGAAUAUCAGUUACCAAAGUAGGAUGAAAGGAUGUUGGGUAGAUCAAAACAACAAAUGUCCAUUACAGCAAUUAACAAAAGUUAGGGAGUGGGGAAGUCUGAGUGCUAAUAUGGAUUUCAAAACAACUUUAAAAAUGGCUUCAAACAUUUUAUGCUUUUUGUAAUUUAGUCAUUUUAAUAUUAGAUAAAUCUUCCUGUAACUGAAAGUUCUUGAGUUAAAGAAAAAUAUUCGGUAGUUCAGCUCUUCCUUCAAUUUUAUUAGUUGCUUUUUCUUUUGUUCAAGUGAAAUAAACAUAAAAAUAAUUUUAAAAUAUUAUGUAUCAUAUCCUUCGAUUUAACAUAAUUCUAUCUAGCUGUUCUUAUAUUUUCUCUGAUAUAUUUUUAAAAGCUUUCUGGAAUAUUAUUAACCUUGAAUAUUUCUAGUUGAUGAGUUUAUGAGUGAUUUAUUGCUUCCUUUUCUCUUUCAGUAUUGCUAGAAUUAAUUUUAUUGACUUUGCCCCUUUGCAUAAAGACCUUGAAGGUCACAUGCUGAAAUCGCCCUCUACUAAAACAAACUCAUAGAAAUAAUGGGGAAGAUAUUUCAAAACAUUGCCAUAUGCAUAGCCAUCCUCACAACCAAGAAAAGCGCCUCUCCAUGAACUAAAACCUAUGAGUCAUUGGUACAGGUAGGGAAAAUCUAGGUAAACCACGGUAAUACACUGAGGCUGGCACCACCACAGGCCAGGACAACCGUUGUCACAAAGCCAGGACAGAAUCUCCCAGCCAGAAAGUGUUGCCCUGAGGCUGAAGCCAAAUUCAUUUUGCCCCCAGUUGGCCAGACCAAAGCCUAGAACUAAAAAACCCAUACCUCAGGGUUUGUCAGCAUUGGCACUGCUGGCUUUUUGGGCUGGACAACCAUUUAUUGUGAGAGGCUUCUCUAUGCACUGUAGGAUGUUUAGCAGCAUCCUUGGCCCUACUCCCUAGACGCCAGUAGCAAAUCCACCACCCUCCCUCCCCUACCCCAGGGUUGGUUGUCAGUUGUGACAACCAAAAAUGUCUCCAGACAUCGCCAAAUGUCCCUUGGGGGGUAAAAUCACCACCACCAUACCUCUUUUGACUAAAAGAGUUUCCAGAAUAGUGGCAGAAUAUAUAGGUCAAGCAUAACACAUUACAAUCAAGAUUCAGAACAUCAAAGAUUCUUUUUUAAUCCUAAAAGAAAAAGUUUGGAAAAUCUACAAAAAGAAGUGUGAAUUUGACAAUAACUAUUUCACUAGCAAGGGUAGACGUAAGCAGAAUACAGGUAGCAUAUUCAAACUGCUGUGGAAAAACAACAUCAAACCUAGACUUCUCUCCCCAAACUAUCAUUCAGAGUCGAGGGCAAAAUAAAUAGAUUUUCUGACUUGGAACAAGUAGGAAUAAUGUACUUAUAGUAUUCAUCUUCAUACAGGGAUGGACUAUAAGUGAUUUUUAAAAAACUUCCUACUUGUUCCAAGUCAGAAAAACUAUUCAUAUAGGGAUGGGCUAUUAGCAAGAGUAUAUGAAUAACGUACUAUAACAAGAAAAAAUGAAUUGAGAAGAAAGUAGUGGUUUUAAGAAGGAAAGGAGAACAAAUAAAUUAGUGAAACAUAAGGUUAAGUCUAUACAUAUUAUUUUCUAAUUGCCUAUUAUGUCAGACUACAUGUAGUUAGAAAAUACGAUGAAAGAAAAAGCCAUAUUAUAAUUCCAACAAAAAGAUAAAAUAAUUAAGAAUAACUGCAACAAGAAAAUAUAAGUUCUGCAACAAUAAAACUAUACAAUGAAACUAAAGAGCACAAAAAAGAACUUAAACAGAUAAAAAGCAGACCACGUUUUUGGAUAAGAAGAUUAAAAAUUAUAAAUAUAUCAAUUUUCACUGUUAAUCUAUAAAUUCAGUGUAAUCCCAAUAAAAAUGCCAACAGGUUUUCCCCAAUAGCAUUGAAAUGAUUUUAAAAUUUAAUGAAGGCCAAGCAUGGUGGCUCACUCCUGUAAUCCCAGCACUUUGAGAGGCCGAGGCAGGUGGAUUGCCUGAGUCCAGGAGUUCCAGACCAGCCUGGACAACAUGGUGAAAUCCCGUCUCUAUUUAAAAUGCAAGAAAUUAGCUGGGUGUGGUGGUGUGCACCUAUAGUCCUAGCUACUCGGGAGGCUGAGGUGGGAGAAUCACCCAAGCCUUGGGAGGUCGAGGCUGUAGUGAGCCAAAAUCACAUCACUGCACUCCAGUCUGGGCAGCCAGAGUGAGACCCUGUCUCAAAAAAAAAAAAAUUAUUGGAAACUACGAGGCAAGAAUAUCCAAGAAAAAUCUAGAAAAGAAGAAACCUGAGUGAGUCAGCAUGACCAAAUAUUAAAACAUCUUAUAAAGCUACAAUAAUUAAAACAAUGUGGUGCUGAUAUGUGGAGGGUCAAUGGAACAAGAUGAAAUGGCCAAAAAUAAAUUUAAAAUACAUGUUGAAAUGUAUUAACAGCAUAUGUUAAAGUUAAGUUAUGUUAACUUUAUAUGUUAAAUUCAAGUUAAUUGGGGAAAGAUGGAUUAUUCAAUAUAUGAUGAACAACUCUGUCACCCAGCUAAAAAAAAUUAAGCUUGGGCCAUAUGCCAGACUAGAUACCAAAAUAAAUUCCAGGAGGACCAAGUUUUUAAAAGUAAAAAUAUGGAAUCAUGGAAGUGCAUGAAGAAGAAGUAGCACUUAAAAAAAUAAUAAUCUCAGCAUGGGGAAGGUCUAAGUAUGGCCCUCAAUCAGAAACCAGGAAGGAAAAUAUUGACUAUUUUAAACAAAAUUAUCUCUGUACCAAAAACAGCAUAAAAGGUCAAGAAACAACACACUGGAAAAAGAAUUGCAAUGAAUAUCACAGCCAAAUAGUUAAUUUCUUAUUUUCAAAAAAUAGCUUCUACAAAUCGAAGAGAAAAAUUCUAAGGUCUCAAAGGAAAAAUGAGCAAAGGAUUUGACAGGUGGUAGAAUACAGAAAAAGAAUUUAAAAUAGCUCCUAAAGAUAUGGAAACAUUACUCAUGAUAGCAGAAGUAUCAAUUGACAAAAUUACUCAGAUUGGUAACAAACUUUAAGGGGGAAAGCACUUCCAUGCAUUGCUGUAAAUUGGUACAUCUUCUACUGAGAACAAUCCGGCAGUAGUUAACAAAAUUGUGAAUGCAUAUAUCUCUUUCUCUAGAAAUUUCUCUUUUGGGAAUUUAUUCUACAUAUAUAUUCAAACGUGUGAAAUACUUCUAUACAGGUGAUUGAAUUUCACUUUAUUCCUAAGAGCAGAAGACUGCAAAAUAGUAAAUAUAUACCCAAAAGGGUCUAAUGGAUUAGUUUUUGGCAUAUCAGCACAUGAUAAUACUAUGAAGCCAUAAAAAAGAGAGAUCUCUAUAUGUAUUGAUGGGGGACCAUCUUUAAGAUAUACUGUGGUGUUGAACAAAACAACAUGCUGAAAAUGUCUCUUAUUCUUUUAGAAUCAAUAUAAGUCUGUGCUUGUAAAUGCAGUAAGUAUCUUUGGAAGUAUACCUAAAAAUUGGUAAUAGUGUUUGACUCCAGGGAAGAACAGAUGGGUGCCAGAGUGAAAAAAAGAUAGCUUUUGCUUUUUAUGACUUUUGGAUUCUGUACCACGUAAUAAUUUUGAUGUAAAUUUUGCUGUGUGUGUUUUUACUUGUUCAUGUAGUGAUUUUAUAAAUUACUCUUUUAAUUUUCUAUCAAUGAAUAUCCUGGGAUAAACCCCUCAUGAUCAUAAUGAAUAAUGAUGUGUGGAGAGUGGGGAGGGUUUACAUAUGAAAAAUGUAGAAAAUACAAAAAGUGUCUAUAUAUACAAAAAUGUAAGUGUUAACAUUUUUAUAUUUGCUUCAAGCUUUUUUUUUAAAUAAAAGAAAUGCAAUAUUGCAAUUAAA